GCAUGGCUGGCGGGCUGUGGGGAAGGCAGGCCUGGGUGGCAGCCGUGUGACAGUGCUCAGCCCCAGCCUGGCAGCGUGUAGCUGGGGGAUCUGGGGCUUUGAGGCAGGGAGGCCUCAGUUUGAGUUGCACUUCUCCAUCUGUGUGACUUUGGCAUGCUCUCUCCAAGCCCCAGCUGACUGGGCCAACAGCGUCUCUGGUAGACUGGGUGUGUACAUGGAAUGAGGCUAUGGUGGCAGGCUGCCCUGCCCCGCACUUGCAUGGUGGUGUCCCUCUUCUCACCCUCCCCAGGGCAUGGCACGGGCAGCAGCACCGUCGGUCAGUGGGCACCCUCUGCCCGUGCAGUGAGUGGGGAGCGGGUGGAGGGCACAGGCGGGCCACACAGGCAGGGGGCUCCGGGGAGCACAGCUGAGGCAGGAGAAGAUGGCCCCCACCUGCCCUUCACCAGCCUCUGGCAGGGGCACUUCACACCAGGUGCUCCCAAUCUGAUGGGGUGCAGACCAGGGAGGAGUUUGUGUCCUCUAAGGUCAUCGGGGCUGGGAGCAAAGAAGGCACAGAGCACAGAAACGAUGCCCAGCACAGCCCAGGGGCUCAGAAGAAGUGGUAUCUGUGCCGAGACUCAGAGGAUAGGUUUAAAGAGAAAGAGUGAUAGAGAACAGGCGUUUCAUCUGAAAUGUGAUUCUGUUCCAUCAGGGAUCCCCAUUCAGCUCAAGCUCCUCUCACUGCAGAAAAAUAUUCUGGUACUACAUUUCAAUUGGCAGCACCCAUCCCCAAGGCUUAUAAAUGUUCCCUCUUGCCCCCGCAUGUGAUCAGCAGCCUCUACGGAGCACCUCCUCUGCAGCAGGCUCCUCAACAACAUAUGUGGCCAGUGCUGCUAUUAAGAUCCCAUUUCACAGGUGGGCAAGCUGAGCCCCAGAAAAGUCAAGUCACUUGCUCAGACUCCUACAGCUGAGGGGACUGGCCCUGGAGGUAAAGCUGAUAUCACUUGGCUCAAAGCCCCAAAGCUCUAUCUCGUGGCUGGUGGCACUAGAGGAGACAAACGAGACUGGCAGAGCAGGUAAGUGGCCAUCAAGAGACCCGCAUUCCCUUCCAGACGGGAUUUGACUGAUAUGGGUCCCUGAACCAUGGAUCCAUAUGUCUUCUUCACUGUUGCACCCCCACAGCUUUGUCAGGGCCUGGCGCCUACAACACACACACACACACACACACACACACACACACUCACAAAUAUGUCAAAUGAUGGCAAAGAAGGUGCCUUCCGGAGCACCUGGCCCCUGUCCACUUGGCCUGUAUUCCCUGACCAGCUGAGGACAGCCAUCCCUCCUGCCCUGGCUCAUGCCAGCUUGUCAGCCUUUGCCAGGGAUCCAGGUGUUUCUGCCCUAUGGCCCUGUACUGGUGGUGGCUGUCCUUAGAUGGGGCUGCAGGGCAGGACAACACCAAGGCAGGCGCCCUGUUCUCUGUGCCAAACCUUGCAUCUCUACGUCUGCAGGUCCUUGUCCUGAGGCUUGGACCAGCCCCUGUAGUUUGACGCCUCAGACUGGAACAGUAUGUGCAUGUAAGCGUGUGUGCACAUCUGUCUGGCUGUCGGCAGUCUCAGGCCCUUGGACAACGGCACUCAGGUGACGGGUCAGCAGGGGACAGUGCAGUGGUGACUAGAGGGGCACUGCAGCCAGGCCACCUGGACUUCAGUCCCCAUCCUAGACAGCACCAGCCACGCUCCCUGCCCCUCUUUCCUCACCUGUAAUACAGGACAUAACAGCACUGAUCUAAGGACUCAGAGACAAUGCGCAGAAAAGUGCUUAGAAUCACGCCUGGCUGAUAGCGCUUGGAGUCUGGCUUUGCUUUUUUCUGUCUGGGUCGGACACUCGCCAACUUCGCUGAAAGGAUCGUGUGGAGCUGCCCAGAGCAGCUGCUGAAAACUGCGUUUCAGGAAUCCUCACGCAACCCGGAAGGAACGCAAGGGCGUGGCCGCUAAACCUGAGGGCGCCCGGCCUGCGCACGCGGACCUGGACUGGAACCCUACUUGCAGGACUGGUCCUGCUCGCUCCUCGUGGCCUCCCUCGCGGGCGCCUUCGGCUCCUCCUUCCUCUACGGCUACAACCUGUCGGUGGUGAAUGCCCCCACCCCGGAAGCACACUUUGCUGGCCAAUAAUGGGUUUGCAAUUUCUGCUGCAUUGCUGAUGGCCUGCUCGCUCCAGGCAGGAGCCUUUGAAAUGCUCAUCGUGGGACGCUUCAUCAUGGGCAUAGAUGGAGGCGUCGCCCUCAGUGUGCUCCCCAUGUACCUUAGUGAGAUCUCACCCAAGGAGAUCCGUGGCUCUCUGGGGCAGGUGACUGCCAUCUUUAUCUGCAUUGGCGUGUUCACUGGGCAGCUUCUGGGCCUGCCCGAGCUGCUGGGAAAGGAGAGUACCUGGCCAUACCUGUUUGGAGUGAUUGUGGUCCCUGCCGUUGUCCAGCUGCUGAGCCUUCCCUUUCUCCCGGACAGCCCACGCUACCUGCUCUUGGAGAAGCACAACGAGGCAAGAGCUGUGAAAGCCUUCCAAACGUUCUUGGGUAAAGCAGACGUUUCCCAAGAGGUAGAGGAGGUCCUGGCUGAGAGCCGCGUGCAGAGGAGCAUCCGCCUGGUGUCCGUGCUGGAGCUGCUGAGAGCUCCCUACGUCCGCUGGCAGGUGGUCACCGUGAUUGUCACCAUGGCCUGCUACCAGCUCUGUGGCCUCAAUGCAAUUUGGUUCUAUACCAACAGCAUCUUUGGAAAAGCUGGGAUCCCUCCGGCAAAGAUCCCAUACGUCACCUUGAGUACAGGGGGCAUCGAGACUUUGGCUGCCGUCUUCUCUGGUUUGGUCAUUGAGCACCUGGGACGGAGACCCCUCCUCAUUGGUGGCUUUGGGCUCAUGGGCCUCUUCUUUGGGACCCUCACCAUCACGCUGACCCUGCAGGACCACGCCCCCUGGGUCCCCUACCUGAGUAUCGUGGGCAUUCUGGCCAUCAUCGCCUCUUUCUGCAGUGGGCCAGCCCUCCCAAGACUUUUUGCAAUGAUCCUGAUUCUGUUCCAAGUGUUUGCAACUGUGGCUUUCUUUUGACUGUAGAACAUGCUGCAUUUCCAGGGCUUUAAAUGCUGGGCUCCCCAUCAGUGUCUAUGGGACUCCCUGGAGGGAAGGCCACCUGCACCUCCCAAUCCCAGAUCACCUGUCAGCCCCUGCCCUCCGCUUCCUCAAUCCAUCUUCAACCCCCUGUGUUGACCCAGCACCUGGGCCUCGCUGGCUAGCAAUGACUUUAGCCACAAGAUGGACCAGGGUUUAGAAGCUUCAUUUAAACUCACAUUGAGAGUGUACAGUUUAAAGCCUCAGGGAACUUACCUGUCUAAGAAAAGCUGCCACUUAGACCAUGAGACCAUCUUGCAUCUUCCUAAGUGGACAGGGAAGAGCAAGUCCCCAGGGGAGCCACCCGGGAAAGUGUGGCAGGAAGAUGCUCAGAGCUGAAUGGCAGAGAGACUCAUGGGCCUGCUCUCCAUGAUUAAAGAAGAGGGAUGGAUCUCCCAGGAGAGGGCCAGGAGGCCGCCUGAGGCAGCUUCUGUGAGGAACAGGUCGAUGUAAGAAGACUUGACAAGGAGUUGAAAUUAGGUGAAAGCAAAGAAAGAAAACAAGAGAGGCAGUUUCCUGCUGCAUAUUUUAUUUGUGUGCAUAACCCCAAGGCAGUGGCAGGGAAGUCUAAUAAAUGAGGCAAAAUAAAAGAGCUUCACCUUUUAAAAAAAGAAGAUCGUUGCCAAAAUGUGUCAAUUCCAGUUUUAAAAAUCACAUGAAGCCCUGACUCUGUGCCUGGCACCAAGUUAAGUCCUCUAUGGGGAGUUUGUGUUUAAAUGGAGUGGACAGAUGCAAACAAGAUGGAGCGGUAAGGCCACUGCCAUUAUCAAGGUGCGAAUUAAGGUCUGAGCACCCCAGAAGAUGGAGCGGUCCUGAUGGAAGAUGCCUCAGCACAUACCUUGCUUGGAAAAAGGACCCCUCUGGAAAGACUGCAGGGGCGUAUCAGCAUUUGACAGAACCUAUGUGGUCGUCUCUGCCUGCCCUGCCUGCCCUCCCUCUCUAUCCCGCAUUCUCCCUGCACUGCAGCCAUCUGGAGCCACAGGCAGCUGCCCCCUGCCCCACACGCACAAACACACACACACACACACAUACACACAUAAAUACACACACACACACACGCUUCAUGGUCUCAGCCUUUGCAUGUGCUAUUUCCCCUCUUGCAACAACCACCCUUAUUCAUCCAUUUGAGGUGUGGCUUCUCAUCUUCAAAAAGUCAGCUCAUACUGCAUCUUGAGACUUUCUUAGAAACAGCCCGCCCCUCUGGGCUCCCACAGCCCCCUAGAUUAACUCCUAGUGUAUCCCCACCCCCACCCCAUUACAAUGGCCAUGGUUGGUCAGUCCUCCUAACAUCAGGGACUGCUUCAAAGACAAGAACCUUGUUUCUAUCACCUGUAUCCAAACACACAGCCUGACAGUGGGUCAGCACUCAAUAAAUGCUUGUAUUUUUCAUGAAUUCAUUCAAAACAUACUCAUUAAGUUCCUACUGUGUGGUGUGUGGUGUUUUCUACCACCACAGCUCACACCAAAUGUGUGUGUGUAUUUUGACACCAAACACAUGUUUUCCACACCACCUCUUCAAUUUGUCUCCACCAACAACUGGGUGUCCAACAAUUCAGCUCAAUUCUGACACUGCCUCCCCAGAGUGUCAGAAAGAGUUAAAGGGUUCAAUCCCACAAGACUGCCCUCACUUCAGACACCAACCAAAAACAGAGUCCCAGGGAGCCGGCACUUCUGCUCUGCUGACUACAAAUUCAGGGGUUCCCAAGGCUACCCUCAGGUUUGAUAAUUAUUUGCUAGCAUGACUCCCAGAACUCAGGAAAGUGCCCUACUUACAAUUACAGCUUUAUUAUAGAGGCUGCAACUCAGAAACAGCCAAGUGGAAGAGAGGCAUACAGAAGGUAUGGGGGUGCAUCACGGGGCAUGGAGCUUUCAUGCCCUCUGUGGAUACACCAGCCUCCCAGCACUUCAGUGCGUUUACCAACUGGGAAACACCUCAACCCCAUCAUUUAGACGUUUCUAUGGAGGCUCCAUUAUAUAGGCAUGAUUGAUUCCAUCACUGGCCACUGGUGACUGAACUCAGCCUGCAGCCCCUCUCCCUUCCUUAGAGGCUGGAAGAUGGAGCUGAAGGUUCCAACCCUCCAAGCAUGGCCAGCGCUGCCUUGAAACCAUCUAAUGACCCACCUGAGUCACCACAUUAGGGGUUCAUUAUAAAUGACAAAAGCCACUCUUGUUACUCCAGAAAUCCCAAGGCUUUUAAGAAAUCUGGGCCAAAAACUAGGGACAAAAAUCAAAUAUAUAUAUAUUGCAAUUUUAUAUAUAUAUAUAUGUGUGUGUGUGUUAUGCCACAGUGCCAGCCCUGGGCUGGGAGUUGAAGAUAAAAGGAUGAGCAAGACAGUGUCUCUACCCCCACAGAGGAAGAGGAGAGGGACAGGGCACAGUUGAGAAUGACCACUAUAGACAUUCUAUAGGAGGAAGGGGGCUGGCACUCUCAACUGCAUUGGCUGCUGGCCCCGGCUGACCCCGAGGAGGAAACCCUCCUGCAAACAGUGUUGAGAAUCCCAGCCAGGCUCUUAGGAUUGCACACAGCAGGUGUGCCCCAACAGGAGCCUGGUGAGAUCCAGAAGGGGUAAAGGCUGUGUCCAGCAGACCCAGAAGAGCCUGGGACAGGAAGAUGGCAGGAGCAUCAGAUAACAUAAAGAGUCAAAGCCACCCACUUGUAUGACAUUAUCUCAAUGCCAGGCCUGCACCUGCAACAUCUGGAAAGAAGAAACCAUGAAACAUCCUGGCCCUGCCCUGCAAGUGAAAGGGCUCAGUCCUUUAACUCCUCCUAUGCUGGAGGAGCCCACAGAAGAGACAGACCUGGGAAUGAAUAAGUAUUGCUUACUGGAUUUACAGGAGGCAGGAGAGGGAAAAAAGAAGGAACCCAUGUGUGUCAAAUGCCUGGGAUUCGUCCAAACAUUGUUCAUACAUGAUCCCUUUCAAUUCUCUCAUGCCAGCAAGGUUGAAUCCAUGAUCUCAAAAGAGGCAAGGUGGAGUCCAGACUCAACCCUAGAUAUGUCUGCCUCUGAAUCUCCUGCCAGGGGGGCAGGCACUACCCCAAGUUGGGUGGGAGGGCUCUGUGCACCAGCCUGCACUGCCCCAAGAGGGAGCUCAGCCAGCAGACAGCAAGGUCUCCCUGCCUGGGAUGGGGUGCUUAGGCAGGUACGGGCACAUUCUUACUUGUUGAAUGAAUAAACAAGUGAAUGAACAAAUAAUAGAUGAAAGAAAGAACCCUAUCCGUGGCCUUGGCCUCACCCCAAUUACCUUAAGUAUCCCAGCACUUUAGGGGGAGUCGAAUCAGAUGUCUCCUUUCCCCUCAAAAGUUAGGGAAUUGUGUGCAAAGCAGAAUGACAAAUUGCUUUCUAAUCCUCCGGACCAAGCAGAAAGUAUUGCAUAGAAGGAAUAAAUAUAUGCACAUUAAAAUAACUAUAGCUAUAAGUUAAGAGACAUAAUGACACCAACUUGGCAUAUAGUCAUAAUUUUUGAAAAACUGUUUAAUGAAAAUUAAAUGGAAAUGUCUCACAAAUCUAGACUUAAAACUAAAUAGUAGCCAUUGCUCAGGACACAUCAAUGUCUCUAAAAUGAAUUCGUACAGAAGGUGAGAAUUAACUCCAGCAUUGGUGCUAGUCCCUGUCUAGAAACAAAGACUCAGACUCCACACCCAUUACCACACAGGCUUUUAGGGAAGGGACUUAAAAGAUGAGCUAUCUAAAACUACCCUGUGAACUCUAAACUAUUAUAUAAAUGUGAAAUUUCAUCCAGGUCCAGCAGGAAUCAGGGAAUCAGGAGAUACAGUCAAGAGGGUUUUAUUUGUUUGUUUGCUUGUUUGUUUGUUUGUUUUAGAGAUAGGGUCUCGCUCUGUCACCCAGGCUGAAGUGCAGUGGUGUGAUCAUGACUCACUGCAGCCUCCACCUCCUGGACUCAGGCUAUCCUCCCACCUCAGCCUCCUGAGUAGCUGGGACAAGUGCAUGCCACCAUACCUGGCUACUUUUUAAAUUUUUUUGUGGGGAUAGAGUCUUGCUAUGUUUCCCAACCUGGUCUGGAACUCCUGGGCUCAAGUUAUCCUCCCACCUUGGCCUCCCAAAGUGCUGAGAUUACAAGCAUGCACUGCCAGGAUUUUAAAAGCAGUUCUGUGAAUGGACUAUUUAUAGCCCUGUGGGUAGGGAUAGGGAACCAGAGAGAGAUGGAGGCCCCUUGGGACGAACAACAGUGGGAAGCUUCAACCACCUCAGGGGUAAACUAAUUUUCAUUAAAUUUCUCCAUAACAGAAGAAUAUAAACACUAAGAAGUAAGAUUUCAUCAGGUAGGGCUAAGCUUUUGCAGCUCUGCAAACCAUUGUGAUAUUUAAGACUUCUUGCCACCUCCCAAGAACCAGUUCUCACCCCUGUCGACAAAGCAUGGCAGAGAUUCAUUUCCGCUUUUAUCAAAAACUAUUUUGAGAUUCUGAGAACCAAACAGGCAAAUUCAACAAUGUGAUGUGCUCUUGCCUAUGGCUUUGUUUGGUGCCCCAUGUCAGACCCCACACUCUGAUGUCCUUUUACAGGGCAAUGCCCAGUGCCAAUGGAGGUUAAGUCAAUAACAUUGUAAUUAGUCCUUCAGCCCUGGGAGCACAAAGAGGAAUAAGAAAUGUCCCAAUCAGGAGCUUGGAGUUCAGUUUCCAAGUAAAGAAGAGGAAGAAGUAGUCAUUGGCUUUGUCACUGGGGGGAAAAGGGGAGGUGGAUAGAGGAAGUUGAGACUCAGAGCGGUUAAGAGCUUUACCUGGAUUACACAGCAGUGAACCACAAUUCCACUUCCUAUCAGUUUGACUCCAGAGCCAGAGUUCUUAAGGUCUACAAUAGGCAACUAAGCUAAAGGCAGGUCCCAGGUACUAAGGGAGCACAGAGGAGAUGUGUGUCUGGGUGAAUGGAUGUCAGGUUACCUAGAGGAGGUACAACUUAGACUGAUUUCUAAAUAUCGAGUCAGAGCAAGCAGAGCCACCAAGUAUGGGUUCUCAGGGUGUGCACUGCACAAGAAGACAUUUCUAAAGACACAGCAUCCCAUCUGAGACAGACGCUAACCUAUGGCCAUUUCUAAAGACACAGCAUCCCAUCUUAGACAGAGAGUAACCUAUGGCCAUUUCUAAAGACACAGCAUCCCAUCUUAGACAGAGAGUAACCUAUGGCCAUUUCUAAAGACACAGCAUCCCAUCUUAGACAGAGAGUAACCUAUGGCCAUUUCUAAAGACACAGCAUCCCAUCUUAGACAGAUGCUAACCUAUGGCCAUUUCUAAAGACACAGCAUCCCAUCUUAGACACUAACCUAUGGCCAUUUCUAAAGACACAGCAUCCCAUCUUAGACAGAGAGUAACCUAUGGCCAUUUCUAAAGACACAGCAUCCCAUCUUAGACAGACGCUAACCUAUGGCCAUUUCUAAAGACACAGCAUCCCAUCUUAGACAGACGCUAACCUAUGGCCAUUUCUAAAGACACAGCAUCCCAUCUUAGACAGACGCUAACCUAUGGCCAUUUCUAAAGACACAGCAUCCCAUCUUAGACAGACGCUAACCUAUGGCCAUUUCUAAAGACACAGCGUCCCACAUUAGACAGACACUAACUUAUGGCCAUUUCUAAAGACACAGCGUCCCACAUUAGACAGACACUAACUUAUGGCCAUUUCUAAAGACACAGCAUCCCACCUUAGACACUAACCUGUGAGAACAUGGGUGCCGAUGUGGGGAUGUGAGGUCUCCCAGCCAGGUUCUGACACAACAGGACUGCACCAUCUCCUACAUCAACUCACAAGCAAAACAGUCAUGCACACAGCUGGGAUUACACAACAUCCACAUAUACUGAUUCACACACAUGCACAUACACACAUGUGCACUCCGUUCUCCAGAUGGCCUCUGAGCUUCCUUUCUAGCCCACUCUCAGAGGCCUGAUUCUCAUCCUCUGCGCGGUUCCAAAACUGGCAUGGUGCUCCACUUUGUGGGAAGGGCACAGAGCUUAGGUGUACACUGGCUCACGGGUGGGGUAAGCAGACAGCUGUGGGGGUACACAUGUGCAUCUGCAGGGCUGCUGCCAUCAGAGAGGGCAUCUGGAGAACUCCCCUGGCAAGGCUGGGCCUGGCCACAGGGUGUGAUCAUUCUGUUUAUUCAAUAAUGUACUAACUUGUAAAAUAUUUUAUUUGAGAAAGGGGCAUUUUUUUUUAAUAGCAAAAGUGCCAUUUGAGCUAGAAGUGGACCUGGAGGUAGCCAGCUAAAGGGAAAAGGAGGAAUGUCUGAGUAGAGGACAGACAUCAGAGAGGAUGCUAAUGGAAGCCUAGGACACAUGUAAAACUGGAGAGACGCUCUGGAGUAAAAGGGCCUCAGGGGACAUCAGGGUGCAGGGAAAGUGGUGGCCAGAUCAUCGUGGGCCUCACAGGCUGAAAUAAUUAAACUUUGUCCUUGUGGAAGUGGGCAGCCACCAAAGAAUUUUGAGCUGGGACAUAGCAUUAUCACACUGGUGUUUAAAAAGUCUGCAGAGGAGGGAAUAAACCAGAGGUAAAAUGUGGAAUAUGGGAGAGGCUUGGGAAGAGUGAAUUCAGAAAGAUCACUAAGGAAUUUGUAUCGGUUAGCUAUGACUGUGUAACAAAUAACCGCCAAGCCUCAUGGAUUAAACAACAACCAGUUAUUAUUGCUCGCAAGAGUUAGUCAGUGUGGCAGUUUUGCUCUUCUGGCCCAGGCUUCUUUGAUCUCAGCUAGAUGAUUUCCUCCUAUCUACAUCCAGCUGGCAGGUCAUCUGGGCACCAGCUAGUCCAAAGUAGCCUCACUCAUUGGUCUGGCACUGAGAAGGGUAACUUGACCACAUGUCCAUCACUGUCCCACAGACUAGACCAGGUUUGUUUAUAUGAUGGUGGCAAAGUUGCAAGAAAAGAAGGGGAAGUGUGCAAAACUGCCUGAGGCCUGGGCUUGGAACUCCACACUAUUUCUGCUGCAUUCUAUCAGCCAAAGCAAGUCACAAAGCCCGCCCAGAUUCAAGGGAUGGGGAAAGACUUUCCCUCCCAUUGGAGGGGCUGCAAAGAACUGUGGCUAUUCUACAAUUGCCUGGAGGCAGUAACUGUAGAAUAGGCAAGAGAUGAGAAUUAUGGGCUUUCCUUCACUUACCCCCAUUCCACAAAUAAUCACUGAGAGCCUACUAGAAAGUGGGCCUCCUUCUAGGCCUGGAGAUGCAGUGGAGGAGCAAACACACAAACACACACACUCACAUGCAUGUGCACACACAUAGAGUCUCUGCCCUUAGGGAUCUUACCUUCAAUAACAGUCAUGGGUCAGGGUCCCCACUGGGAACAUAUGGUACACUCAAACUGGAGUAUUCUGAGGAAUGUUCAAUAAGGACACAAAUUGCUAUGGUGCAAAAAGGCUAUAGGGGAAUGUUGAAGACCUUGACCAUUCCAGCAGUCUCAACAUAUUAUGGUCAUUUCCAAGGGUCCACCCCUCUAGCUGUUAGCUGUGAAGAAAACAAAGCAACUUAAUGAAAGUUAAUUCAUCAAAAGUCAAUGCACUGAGAGGUCACAUUGCUGAAAGUCAAAUCAUAGAGAAACACAAUUUGCUGGAUUUACCUUAUCUCUUUUAACUAUUUAUGAACAAUGUACAUUUUUGUGCAUAGAAUGGAAUGGUUCUAACAGCUUUGAUCAGUUUCUAAGUUCUUCAUCAUGUCUGCGUAGUGAAUUCUGUAGAAUGUUUUUUUUGUUGUUGUUCCUUCUGCUUCAGUUCCCUGUUGUUAUAGCUGGAGGUUAGUAAACAGAGAGAAGCCUCAGCCAAGUGGCAUAAAAUAUACUUUUAUCCACAAAAAGAAUAUAUAUAUCUUUCCCUUUCCAAAUCCAUUUUAUUCCAGAAAUUUAUGCAUACAACAGGAAAUAGGAUUUGGAUAGCAAGCGAUAUAGCAACACAUUUAUCGAAUUUAUUCAUUCAAGCGUUUGGAAAACAGGAGUCUGGAUAGCAAAGGUUCAGAUAGUGAGAGGGAUUCCUGCACAUUCACAGACUGGGUUUCUUUUGUUAACAUAUUUUUAUUCAAAAAUGCAUUUACCAGUCUUUGCUUUUUGAUGAAUUGACCUUGAGCUGACAAUGUGACUUUCAUUCAUGGCAUUUCUGAGCCCUCAUUCCUGGCCAGGACACAGAGGUACCACAUCCCACUGCACCCUGCCCCAACUCACAGGAGAGAUGGUCUGGGAUGCUCUUGGAAUUUUGCUGUGACUUUCCCAAAAUCUACAGUAAGUUGGACAAGUCCCUGUCCCUCUCUGGCCUCAGUUUCACCAUCAGUGAAAUGAGGGGAUGAACCAGAUUAAGGGCUCUCUAACUACAUGGCUGCACUUCAGAACCCCCUUCCCUGGGGAAACAUCCCCCACCCGGGUCCCUGGAUGAGGAGGGACCUCAUCCAGGUUCUGCUGAGGAGGCCUAGGGACAGCAUUUCCACAUAUUUCCUGAAUGAUUCCUCAGCAGCCAUCCCAGCCCAAGCCACUUUCCUGAGCAUGGAAGCCUCCAGAAUUGGUGGCCAGAUCUACCAACCUUGUGGCUGUGCAAUUCACCUCAUUCAAUCCUCAUGGCAGCCCAGGAGACAGACCAUCUUAUUCCCACUUUGCACAUGAAGGGCUGAGUUUCUGAGAGGUCAUAACUCAUAGGUUUUAUGGGGCAGGUGCCCCUGAAGUCAGUGGGUUGGCAGUGUUUGUGCUCUUAGCUACUGUAAUGGGUUGAGUAGUAUCCCCCAAAGAUUCUUGUUCUCUCAGAACCUCAGAAUGUGACCUUGGUUAGAAAUAAGGUCAUUGCAGAUUACUCAGUUAAGGAUCGCAAGAUGAAGCCAUCCUGGAUUUAGGGUGGCCCCUAAAUUCAAUGUCUGGUGUCCGUAUAAGACAAGGAGAGGACACAGGGAAGAGAAGGGCAUAUGAAGGUGGAGGCAGAGAUUAGAGCGAGCGAUGCAUCUAGAAUCAAAGGAACACCAAGGAUUGCCAGCAGCACCAGAAGCCAGGAGAGAGGCGUGGAUGGUUUCUCCCUCAGAGUCUGCAGAGAGAACCAACUCUGCCAACACCUUGAUUUUAGACUUCUGCCUCUAGAACAAUGACAGAAUAAAUUUCUGUUCUCCUAAGACCCCAUGUUUGUGGUGAUUUGUGACAGAAGCCCUAGAAAACGAAUAUAGCCACUAAGUUGGCAGGAAAGUAUUUCCUAAUCCUCUACAUAGCUGUAGAUGCAGGGUACCAGGGCUUUGGAAAUGAGUGAUUUCCACCAUCUGACUCUUAAUGCCAAACAAUGGUGAGUGGGCAAGCUGCCUGCCAAGGUUAUGGUGCACUUUCUGCUUUUUCAAGAAGACCAGGGAACUUUUAAAAUUAAUAAUAUUAUCUUCCAAGCCAGGCACAGUGGCUUGCACUUAUAAUCCUAAUGCUUUGGGAGGCCAAGAUAGGAAGAUCUCUUGAGUCCAGGAGUUGAAGGUUGCAAUGAGCUAAGAUUACACCAAUGUACUGCAACUGGGGUGACACAGCAAGACCCCACACACCCCCCAAAAAAAUCUUCCUAAGUUAAGCACUUGGUCAGCGCUAGAUACUUGGCCACACUCACCCUAAUCCUUACAAAGUCUCCGCAAGGAGACCCUCCUCUCCCCAUGAGGACACCACAGCUCCAGGGAGCCCUGCUUGGGCCACAUCUCAUGGCACAUAGUUUAGGUGGCCCAGCCAGGAUUUGAACGCAUGCCUGCCCAACUCCAAAGUCUCCUUUUUCCAGCCGUUCUCCCUUGCAUUUUCACAUGUUCGGUUUUAGUACUUAUCACUUUCCCGCAGCCUAUGGCAGAGUUAAUUAGUGAGCUUAUCGCCUGAAACUUGAAUGCGAAAACGUGGCAGUGUUCCUUAUGAUUUUUUGCCAAAACCCUCCAGAAAACCUCUCCCCUCAGAAGCAGUCCAAGCAAAUGCUGCUCUGAGAAAGAUUUUGAGCCCUUCAAAGUUUUGGUGCGUAUGCUGGGGUUUUCAACAGAAAUGUAGAAAACCUCAAAACUGGCUCUGCAGUCCUUGAAAUCAGUGACACCUGUCAGGCUCAUAGGUCUUUCUCGUGGUUUCUGUCAGCAGCUGUCUUCCUCUUCACUGUCACUUGGGCAAUCCCUGGGAAUCCAGCUGAGGAAUUUGUCACUUAAUUAUUCCUUGCAGCUGCUGAGAUGGUGAGAACACAGUCCUCUGUUGGGCUGUAUCCAUUUCCUGUGGCUGCUGUGACAAAGUUCCACAAAUGACAGCAAUGUGUUCUCCCACAGUUCUGAGGCCAGAAGGCAGAGAUCGAGGCUUCAGUAGGGAUGCAGUGCCCCUGCAGAGGCUCUGAGGGGAGUCCCUUCCACACGCCUCUCCUGGCCUCUGGCAGCUGCCAGUGCUCCUUGGCUUGUGGCCACAUCACUACACAGUCUCUGCCUCCACCUUCACAGGCCUUCCCCUAUGUGUGCAUCCCAAAACUCCAUCUUCCACACUCUUACAAGGACAUGUGUGAUUGCAUUUAGGACCCAGGUCCUCCUCUCAACAUCCUUAACCUAAUCAUAUGUUUGCCAUUUGAGUAAUAUUUGCACACUCCAGGAUGAGGACAUGGAUGUAUAUUUGUGGGGCCACCACUCAGCCCACUGCACUGGACUAGAGAUAAGCAUCUGUUUUCUCAUAUGCUUUGAUAAACACUUUGGCCUCCUCUACCAAAAACAGUUCAUUCAAGUUAGAUCCUAGUCUAUUGGACACCUACUUACUGUCUGCCAGUCACUGUGCUAGGUCUAAGCUACAGAGAUGAGCAGAGGACAGCCACCAGACCCUUGGGAGAAAGAUUGGCGUAAAAUCAAAUAAGAGUAAUAAUUGACAUAUUGCCAAGCCAUCCCAUCUGCCUGGUGUGUCAGAUAAGAGUCCCAGAGCAGGAAAUGGUUGGCCGUGGUCUAGCAAGGUGAGCAGGGAGGAGUUCACUGGGCAAAUGUGAGGAGGGGGCAUUGUAAGAGGAAGGAGGAGCACAGGAGCCCAGGGCCAGAGGCAGGAGACUGACACUGUGCCUGGAAUUGGGAACCAGCAGCUGGUGAAAGUGCAAAGGUAGACAGAAAUUAGAACACAGAAGGCCUUAAUGUGUAGAACUGCCCUGAAGCCAGUGGGAAGCUACUGUUGGGUUUUAAGCAGGAGGCAUGGACUGACCAGGUUUGCAUGUGAGAAUUGAUUCUAGAAGCUGGGUGGAGACGGAGGUUGAUGCUGAGACCUGAGGCUGGAGACCACUCCCCCGUUCCAUCCACUUCUCAGCCUCCGUUUUCUCUGUGGAAAAGUCCAGAUCCCGACUUAUACUGUCUCUGUCUUACGGAUUAGUGUGAGAGUCAAAUGAGAUCAUUAUUGCCAAUAGGCUCUGUCAAUACAUAGAAUUUAGUUGACCAUUUUCAUUGUCUUCACUUGUGGGUUAAAUAAACACUAAAAUAAAAACAUCAGGGAGCCUGGCUGAGCAGGGAAUAACCUCUUGGAGGAAGGAAAACAUUCCCCUUUAUAUGUCAGCAACUUUGACCCUAGAGGGAAUCAGAACCCAUGCCUUUGGGGGGUGUUCCUGCAGACACAGAGCUGUUCUCCCCCUGGGAACCUCACCACUGCUCAAAAUGUAAUGCAAACAUGAACUGACUUAGUUAUCUCAAUGUUCAAACUUGAAAAAAAAUAAACAUUAUGUUCCAAAA